ACAGGCGAGGGGUUGGGUGGCGGUUGAGACAGCGGCGGUACUGGGAUGGGUAGGUGAGGAUCCCGAGACUGAGUGAGCUUCUGCGCGCGGUGCUUUUGGGAACGCGGGACUGGCAACCUGCGGCGCCAGGAGCUGGGCCGAGGCGCGGCGGCGCGGCUGCGGGCCGCCGUCUGGAUGGGAAGUUACGGCGAAGUCCACCCAGCGUUUCUCAGGCAAUCUGAAGGCAAAUCCUGUUUAGACCCAGGCGAAGGUUCCUGGUGACCCAGGCUCUCACCAGCCAAUUGUCCCUUGCCGUCCUCCUGAGGGUAUCUGGAGCUUCAGUGCUGUGUGCUCUUGGCCUCCACACUGGGGAUGCCACUGACUCCCACUGUCCAGGGCUUCCAGUGGACUCUCCGAGGCCCUGAUGUAGAAACUUCCCCAUUCGGUGCACCAAGAGCAGCCUCACAUGGUGUGGGCCGACAUCAAGAGCUGCGAGAUCCAACAGAAAUGAGGUAUAGGGGAGAGAAGCACUGGUCCACCUGAGAUCUGGCUCCAGGACUUACAACAAGGGGAACUUGGGCAAGUUACAGACUCUGUGUGCCUCCAUUUCUUCAUCAGCAAAACAGAAAGAAUCAUCCCAUAAACUGUAAGGUCAAUGCUGUCAGUGAGUCCCCAAAUUGACUGCACAUCUGAGUCAUAUUAACAAACACAUUCCAGGCCCCACCUGAGCCCUCUGAAUCAGAAUCCCUGCAAGGAGGACAAUGAACUUGUAUUUGCACUGACUUUCCCAGCUGUUUCUUACUUUGAUCAACUUGGGGGUGGGACCCAUUGAGCUGCAUCACAUCAUUCCAAAGCCAAAACACAACAGCAGAACAAGAAUAUUUUCAAUGCAGUCUCUGAAGCAGAGGAGAAACUUUUGAGGGAACCUAGAAGUAAAGGACAUCUGGCUUGCUGGGCUCCAUUUAAACUUUGAGUAUAGCAGAGACACGAGCCCUUCGGGACACAUGCCUGUCGCAGUGACACUCCAACUUCGGAAGAGUGGAAGCCCUAAUUCCAAAUUCAAGCAUGCUUUGAGUAGAAAUGAAGUUUGCCUCUUUUUGCACAGGAAGAUGGCCAAUCUUUCCUAAGCUGCUGACCUUACAAGAAAAAGAAUCGUACUGCUAAGAAUUCAAACUUCAGCAGUCAUGGGGAGCCUUGGGAGGAGCCCGAAUCACUGAUGGAAUCGGACAGUGCAUGGAGAUGGUUCAGCAGGACGAGGUGCUGAAAACUCACCCCUGUGUGACCUCAAGUAAGCCACGUAACUCUGUGAACCUGCAGUUUUAUCAUUUUUAAAAUAAAGAAACAUGACAGAUUUUCAUUAUGACACAGAAUGUCAGGUCUCCCAGAUGCCAGAAAAUACAUUUACUUAAAGCCGUUGAUACGUCUUAAAGCGGUUUCCUUACAGUGUCAUUGGAGGACAGCGUGGAGUGCAGAGAGACAUGCUUUGAAAUGGGAUUGAUCCAGUCCUCCUUCCUUCACUACCACAUGAAUGCUGGGCAGCCCAGGAUCACACUCACUGCACCCUCAACUCAGACCGUUACCUGGCACACUGGCCUCACUCUUGUCGGAGACUGAGCUAUUGGCAGUGCCUUCAGCUCUGAGCUCAGGCACCUCGAACAUUGUUUUUGUCGUUAAGGAUCCUAAAGUGCUGCGGGGACUGAUCACAUUUUUCUCAACAUCCCUGGCCCCACCUCUUCUGCCACAAACGUCAGCAUGGUGGUAUCUGCCGGCCCUUGGUCCGGUGAGAAGGCAGAGAUGAACAUUCUAGAAAUCAACAAGAAAUCGCGCCCCCAGCUGGCAGAGAACAAACAGCAGUUCAGAAACCUCAAACAGAAAUGUCUUGUAACUCAAGUGGCCUACUUCCUGGCCAACCGGCAAAAUAAUUACGACUAUGAAGACUGCAAAGACCUCAUAAAAUCUAUGCUGAGGGAUGAGCGGCUGCUCACAGAAGAGAAGCUUGCAGAGGAGCUCGGGCAAGCUGAGGAGCUCAGGCAAUAUAAAGUCCUGGUUCACUCUCAGGAACGAGAGCUGACCCAGUUAAGGGAGAAGUUACAGGAAGGGAGAGAUGCCUCCCGCUCAUUGAAUCAGCAUCUCCAGGCCCUCCUCACUCCGGAUGAGCCGGACAACUCCCAGGGACGGGACCUCCGAGAACAGCUGGCUGAGGGAUGUAGGCUGGCACAGCACCUCGUCCAAAAGCUCAGCCCAGAAAAUGAUGACGAUGAGGAUGAAGAUGUUAAAGUUGAGGAGGCUGAGAAAGUACAGGAAUUAUAUGCCCCCAGGGAGGUGCAGAAGGCUGAAGAAAAGGAAGUCCCUGAGGACUCACUGGAGGAGUGUGCCAUCACUUGUUCAAAUAGCCACCACCCUUGUGAGUCCAACCAGCCUUACGGGAACACCAGAAUCACAUUUGAGGAAGACCAAGUCGACUCAACUCUCAUUGACUCAUCCUCUCAUGAUGAAUGGUUGGAUGCUGUAUGCAUUAUCCCAGAAAAUGAAAGUGAUCAUGAGCAAGAGGAAGAAAAAGGGCCAGUGUCUCCCAGGAAUCUGCAGGAGUCUGAAGAGGAGGAAGCCCCCCAGGAGUCCUGGGAUGAAGGUGAUUGGACUCUCUCAAUUCCUCCUGACAUGUCUGCCUCAUACCAGUCUGACAGGAGCACCUUUCACUCAGUAGAGGAACAGCAAGUCGGCUUGGCUCUUGACAUAGGCAGACAUUGGUGUGAUCAAGUGAAAAAGGAGGACCAAGAGGCCACAAGUCCCAGGCUCAGCAGGGAGCUGCUGGAUGAGAAAGAGCCUGAAGUCUUGCAGGACUCACUGGAUAGAUUUUAUUCAACUCCUUUUGAGUACCUGGAACUGCCUGACUUAUGCCAGCCCUACAGAAGUGACUUUUACUCAUUGCAGGAACAACACCUUGGCUUGGCUCUUGACUUGGACAGAAUGAAAAAGGACCAAGAAGAGGAAGAAGACCAAGGCCCACCAUGCCCCAGGCUCAGCAGAGAGCUGCCGGAGGUAGUAGAGCCUGAGGACUUGCAGGACUCACUGGAUAGAUGGUAUUCGACUCCUUUCAGUUAUCCAGAACUGCCUGAUUCAUGCCAGCCCUACGGAAGUUGCUUUUACUCAUUGGAGGAAGAACACGUUGGCUUUUCUCUUGACGUGGAUGAAAUUGAAAAGUACCAAGAAGGGGAAGAAGAUCAAAAGCCACCAUGCCCCAGGCUCAACGAGGUGCUGAUGGAAGCAGAAGAGCCUGAAGUCUUGCAGGACUCACUGGAUAGAUGUUAUUCGACUACUUCAACUUACUUUCAACUACAUGCCUCAUUCCAGCAGUAUAGAAGUGCCUUUUACUCAUUUGAGGAACAGGACGUCAGCUUGGCCCUUGACGUGGACAAUAGGUUUUUUACUUUGACAGUGAUAAGGCACCACCUGGCCUUCCAGAUGGGAGUCAUAUUCCCACACUAAGCAGCCCUUACUAAGCUGAGAGAUGUCAUUGCUGCAGGCAGGACGUAUAGGCACAUGUAGGUUUGAAUGAAACUGUAGUUCCCUUUGGAAGCCCAGUCAUAGGAUGGGAAAGUGGGCAUGGCUCUAUUCCUAUUCUCAGACCAUGCCAGUGGCCACCUGUGCUCAGUCUGAAGACGUUGGACCCAAGUUAGGUGUGACACGUUCACACGACUAUGUAGCACAUGCCGGGAGUGAUCUGCCAGACAUUCUAAUUUGAACCAGAUAUCUCUGGGUAGCUACAAAGUUCCUCAGGGGUUUCAUUUUGCAGGCAUGUCUCUGAGCUUCUAUACCUGCUCAAGGUCAGUGUCAUCUUUGUGUUUAGCUCAUCCAAAGGUGUUACCCUGGUUUCAUUGAACCUAACCCCAUUCUUUGUAUCUUCAGUGUUGGUUUGUUUUAGCUGAUCCAUCUGUAACACAGGAGGGAUCCUUGGCUGAGGAUUGUAUUUCAGAACCACUGACUGCUCUUGACAGUUGUUAACCCACUAGGCUCCUUUGAGUAGAGAAGCCAUAGUCCUUCAGCCUCCAAUUGAUAUCAAUACUUAGGAAGACCACAGCUAGACGGACAAACAGCAUUGGGAGGCCUUAGUCCUGCUCCUUUCAAUUCCAUCCUGUAAAGAACAGGAGUCAGGAGCCGCUGGCAAGAGACAGCAUGUCACCUGGGACUCUGCCAGUGCAGAAUAUGAACAAUGCCAUGUUCUUGCAGAAAAUGCUUAGCCUGAGUUUCAUAGGAGGUAAUCACCAGACAACUGCAGAAUGUAGAACACUGAGCAGGACAACUGACCUGUCUCCUUCACACAGUCCACGUCACCACGAAUCACACAACAAAAAGGAGGAGAGAUAUUUUGGGUUCAGAAGAAGUAAAUGAUAAUGUAGCUACAUUUCUUUAGUUAUUUUGAACCCCAAAUAUUUCCUCAUCUUUUUGUUGUUGUCAUUGAUUUUGGUGACAUGGACUUGUUUGUAGAGGACAGGUCAGCUGUCUGGCUCAAUGGUCUACAUUCUGAAGUUGUCUGAAAAUGUCUUCAUGAUUAAAUUCAGCCUAAACGUUUCAUCAAGAACACUACAGAGUCGAUACUGUGAGUUUCCAACCUCAGCCCAUCUGUGGGCAGAGAAGGUCUAGUUUGUCCAUCAGCAUUAUCAUGAUAUCAGGACUGGUUACUUGGUUAAGGAGGGGUCUAGGAGAUCUGUCCCUUUUAGAGACACCUUACUUAUGAUGAAGUAUUUGGGAGAGUGGUUUUUCAAAGUAGAAAUGUCCUGUAUUCCAGUGAUCAUCCUCUAAACGUUUUAUCAUUUAUUAAUCAUCCCUGCCUGUGUCUAUUAUUAUAUUCAUAUCUCUACGCUGGAAAUUUGCUGCCUCAAUGUUUACUGUGCCUUUGUUUUUGCUAGUGUGUGUUGUUGAAAAAAAAACAUUCUCUGCCUGAGUUUUAAUUUUUGUCCAAAGUUAUUUUAAUCUAUACAAUUAAAAACUUUUGCCUAUCA